AUAAAGAUCUGUGACCGGCAGCCCCAGACCUGCCUGCCUUCCUGACUUCUGUUCCAGAGCAAAGGUCAUUCAGCCGCUUGAAUCAGCCUUUUCCCCCCACCCGGUCCCCAACUUUGUUUACCCGAUAAGGAAGGUCAGCAUUCAAAGUCAAGAAGCGCCAUUUAUCUUCCCGUGCGCUCUACAAAUAGUUCCGUGAGAAAGAUGGCCGGGAACUCGAUCCUGCUGGCUGCUGUCUCUAUUCUCUCGGCCUGUCAGCAAAGUUAUUUUGCUUUGCAAGUUGGAAAGGCAAGAUUAAAAUACAAAGUUACGCCCCCAGCAGUCACUGGGUCACCAGAGUUUGAGAGAGUAUUUCGGGCACAACAAAACUGUGUGGAGUUUUAUCCUAUAUUCAUAAUUACAUUGUGGAUGGCUGGGUGGUAUUUCAACCAAGUUUUUGCUACUUGUCUGGGUCUGGUGUACAUAUAUGGCCGUCACCUAUACUUCUGGGGAUAUUCAGAAGCUGCUAAAAAACGGAUCACCGGUUUCCGACUGAGUCUGGGGAUUUUGGCCUUGUUGACCCUCCUAGGUGCCCUGGGAAUUGCAAACAGCUUUCUGGAUGAAUAUCUGGACCUCAAUAUUGCCAAGAAACUGAGGCGGCAAUUCUAACUUUUUCUCUUCCCUUUAAUACUUGCAGAAGCUGUUCCCACCAUGAAGGUUCUCUUGUGAUCCUGGGAAAUGCUAGACCGUGAGCAUCUUGAUGGAGGAUGUGAACUGCCACUUCCUCACAGGCAGCAGGCAGGUGCUGAAUAAGUGCUUGCUGAAUGAAUGAAUGAAUCACGCCAAGGGGCAUGUUACCUGUUCCGCCAAAAUCUGCUGCUGCUGCUGCUGCUGCUGCUGCCUUUGCUCCCGCAGGAACUGUUGCUUCUGCUGCUCUAUCAACUGGGCCCGCUGAUCAAUGAGCAUCUGCUUCAUGAUGGCUGCUUGGGGCUGGCUGCCCAGGAAGCCGGGGCCUGCGGGACUGGCUCCUGAGACCAUGCCACCUGAGCCUGGGGGCACGGAGGACUGCAUGGGGCCUGUGGUUCGGGGAAGUCCAACUGGAUGCUGCUCCUGGGAAGACAAGAGAGAGGGAGAUGCAGGGAUUCCCCAUAGAGACUCACUGCUGUUUGAAGGGAAGCCCCUGGAAAAAGGGAACGGGGCAGAAGUCCCAGCUUAUGGACUGGAGGGUUUUUGAGUGGCACGCAUUGCAUUUCCAUAAACGUAGCUUCAAACCCGACCUUACCUGAGUAGAAUGAGAGAGGCCACAAGGGACAGUAAGAGAGCAUGGCUCUGGGAAGUCCAAGGCCAAGUCCAGUCUGUUUCGGAUGGGACUGACUAUUGCAUAUAGACUGGAUUUUCAACUAACAUCCUGUGUUCCUCCAAGGAAAGGGAAUAAGCCCUCAGGCUGAGCUCACCUAAAGUCUGGAACACGAGACACAUCCUGACCUCACCUGUUAAUCCUUAUUUCUUACUGUCUACUUGGCCAAAAUGGACGUCUUCUUUGCAAGUAGGAGGGACAUUUGCAGAAAACUGCAGGAAUUUGUUAAUCAACAGAUCUGAUAUUUGAUGGAAUUCUAACGAGUUGCAACAUUUGAGAGCUUAGAUAUAUGUCAGAAAGAAAAAUCCUCCUGGCCAGAGUUGUUGAUGGUGAGAACUGGGAAUGUUUUACACCGAUCAAAGCUAUGUAAUCUCCUAAUAUUUUUAAAAAUAGAAUUGAGUCGGCCGGGCGCGGUGUCUCACGCCUGUAAUCCCAGUACUUUGGGAGGCCCAGUACUUUGGGUGGAUCACGAGGUCAGUUCGAGACCAGCUUGGCCAAGAUGGUGAAACCCUGUCUCUACUAAAAAAAAAAAAAAAAAAAAAAAAAAAAAAAAAUUAGCCAGACAUGGUGGUGGGCACCUGUAAUCCCAGCUACUCGGGAAGCUAAGGCAGAGAAUUGCUUGAACCCGGGAGGCGGAGGUUGCAGUGAGCCGAGGUCGCGCCACUGCUUUCCAGCCUGGGCGACAGAGUGAGACUCUUUCUCAAAAAAAAAGAAUUGAGUCUUCUAUGUCUGGGAUAAUUUAAACAUGGGGUGUUGGAUUGGGUCUCUUGAUUCUAUAAUUAUAUGUCAGCCAGUCGAAUGAUGGCAACUUUUAAGGACUGGUCCUUAGGGAAGAGGAGGUCAAGUGGUAAAGACCUAAUUCCACACAGCCCAGGUGACUACAUGGAGAAUGUGCUCAAAGGCGAAGUUUAUGCUCUGAGCUGGACAGUGUAGACUAUUAGGGGAAAACAGUGAAUGGGAAGAAAAGGUGUGUGGCCCAGAUUCAAUUUCUAGACACUUCCUUUCCUAUUUUUUCUACCAAGACUACCUAGCAGUGGCAAGUAUGUUCUGAACAUUCUGCAGAAAUUCCUUCUACCUCACUGAAGUUUCAAGUAAUUAAUGUGAAAUGGAGGAGUUGACACAGAUUAAAUGGGCACACAUAUAAGGACAUUCACAGUCAUUUUGUGAAGCACUAUUAUGAGACCUAAAUAGCAAGAAGCAAAUGUGAAUAACUCUGUCAUUUAAAAAUUUUUAAAUCCAAAUUGGAUUUUAACAUUUUUCUUCUUUUUACUUUAUUGCCUUUCCAAUGCAGAUACCGUUAAACAUAUUGGCAGUUUUUUCUCAAAGCAAAUAGGUGAAGUUUCUCUCUGUCUCUCCUAGAGAGACCGUCCUGGAUUUGAUUCCCUAUGGCUUGGGCUUGUGUUCCUCCCUUCCUUCUGUGGUGUGCUGUAGAACCAUGCAGGCUUCCCUCUCCACUAUGACUGACUUCAACUGCAUCUUCAGUUGCUCUUCUUCCCUCCAAACAAAACAAAACAGCAAAGCAAACAAAAGCCAAACCAAACCAAAACGCUACUCCUCUUACCCUAGAAACAAUCACCCAAGAAGCUCUGGUUUGUUCGUGCAGUAGCUUAGGUCACACAAUCAAUGAAUGGAAGACACAGAACUAGCAGAACUAGAACGCUAUUUUUUUUUUUUUUGUAACAGAUAGCUUGUCUUUACUUUUUUAAAAAAUGUAACUUAAAAUUAAAAAAAAAAUUUCCAUAAGUUAUCGGGGUACAGGUGGUAUUUGGUUACAUGAGUAAGCAGAACGCUGAUUUUGAUUCUCAAUUCAGUAUUCCUACUAGCUCAGGCCUCUCCCAGGCAGUGUCUUCAUGGUGUUAAGUGUGCACCUAAGAACAGCCUGUAGACCUAUAUACUGUGUCUCUCAUAAGUGUACUGCGUUCUAUUUUUUAUGUGUAAAUGCUGUAGCUGAAAUUAAUAAAAUGUUUUGCCUUUGUGUAUUUUCUCUAUAAAUACACAAAGACAGCUAGGAAAUAUUUUUGAUGUUAAUAAAAAGAUCUUACACUAAAAAAUGCCAGGAACCUUUGUGCUACCAAAAAGUUUACUUCAGGACUAACCCUUGCAGGGGCCUAGAUAUUUCAGGGUCUUCCCUUUUCCCCCAAAUAUUUGCUACCUGUUUUCCAAGCCCUUCCUUCCAGUGAAAUAAAGCUGUUUCUUGGCACCUUUAGGGACAAA